UUGCGCAUUGGAGGUCAGAGGACAGCGAGAUUCUCGCCCUGAGCAACGGCCUGACGUCGGCGGAGGGAAGCAGGCGCAGGCUCCGUGAGGAGGCAAGAAUCCGGGCUUUGCCCCUGCAAUCAACCCACGGAAGCUCCGGGAAUGGCGGCCAAGCACGCGGAUCCUGACGUUCACAUAUCUCAGGGAGUUGAUGACCUUGUUUUCAGAAGGUGACUCAGGUCAACACAGGGGCCCCCAUCUGGUCGACAGAUGCAGUGGUUCUAGGAUCUGCCAAGCAUCCAGGUGGAGAGCCUGAGGAAUCAGGAGCUCCAGGAACCAGGCAGUGAGGCCUUGGUCUGAGUCAGUGUCCUCAGGUCACAGAGCAGAGGGGACGCAGACAGUGCCAACACUGAAGGUUCUGAGGGGGACAGGCUGACAAGUAGGACCCGAGGCACUGGAGGAGCAUUGAAGGAGAAGAUCUGCCUGUGGGUCUUCAUUGCCCAGCUCCUGCCCGCACUCCUGCCUGCUGCCCUGACCAGAGUCAUCAUGCCUCUUGAGCAGAGGAGUCAGCACUGCAAGCCUGAAGAAGGCCUUGAGGCCCGAGGAGAGGCCCUGGGCCUGGUGGGUGCGCAGGCUCCUGCUACUGAGGAGCAGCAGACCGCUUCUUCCUCUUCUACUCUAGUGGAAGUUACCCUGGGGGAGGUGCCUGCUGCCGACUCACCGAGUCCUCCCCACAGUCCUCAGGGAGCCUCCAGCUUCUCGACUACCAUCAACUACACUCUUUGGAGACAAUCCGAUGAGGGCUCCAGCAACCAAGAAGAGGAGGGGCCAAGAAUGUUUCCCGACCUGGAGUCCGAGUUCCAAGCAGCAAUCAGUAGGAAGAUGGUUGAGUUGGUUCAUUUUCUGCUCCUCAAGUAUCGAGCCAGGGAGCCGGUCACAAAGGCAGAAAUGCUGGAGAGUGUCCUCAGAAAUUGCCAGGACUUCUUUCCCGUGAUCUUCAGCAAAGCCUCCGAGUACUUGCAGCUGGUCUUUGGCAUCGAGGUGGUGGAAGUGGUCCCCAUCAGCCACUUGUACAUCCUUGUCACCUGCCUGGGCCUCUCCUACGAUGGCCUGCUGGGCGACAAUCAGGUCAUGCCCAAGACAGGCCUCCUGAUAAUCGUCCUGGCCAUAAUCGCAAUAGAGGGCGACUGUGCCCCUGAGGAGAAAAUCUGGGAGGAGCUGAGUAUGUUGGAGGUGUUUGAGGGGAGGGAGGACAGUGUCUUCGCACAUCCCAGGAAGCUGCUCAUGCAAGAUCUGGUGCAGGAAAACUACCUGGAGUACCGGCAGGUGCCCGGCAGUGAUCCUGCAUGCUACGAGUUCCUGUGGGGUCCAAGGGCCCUCAUUGAAACCAGCUAUGUGAAAGUCCUGCACCAUACACUAAAGAUCGGUGGAGAACCUCACAUUUCCUACCCACCCCUGCAUGAACGGGCUUUGAGAGAGGGAGAAGAGUGAGUCUCAGCACAUGUUGCAGCCAGGGCCAGUGGGAGGGGGUCUGGGCCAGUGCACCUUCCAGGGCCCCAUCCAUUAGCUUCCACUGCCUCGUGUGAUAUGAGGCCCAUUCCUGCCUCUUUGAAGAGAGCAGUCAGCAUUCUUAGCAGUGAGUUUCUGUUCUGUUGGAUGACUUUGAGAUUUAUCUUUGUUUCCUGUUGGAAUUGUUCAAAUGUUCCUUUUAACAAAUGGUUGGAUGAACUUCAGCAUCCAAGUUUAUGAAUGACAGUAGUCACACAUAGUGCUGUUUAUAUAGUUUAGGGGUAAGAGUCCUGUUUUUUAUUCAGAUUGGGAAAUCCAUUCCAUUUUGUGAGUUGUCACAUAAUAACAGCAGUGGAAUAUGUAUUUGCCUAUAUUGUGAACGAAUUAGCAGUAAAAUACAUGAUACAAGGAACUCAAAAGAUAGUUAAUUCUUGCCUUAUACCUCAGUCUAUUAUGUAAAAUUAAAAAUAUGUGUAUGUUUUUGCUUCUUUGAGAAUGCAAAAGAAAUUAAAUCUGAAUAAAUAAUUCUUCCUGUUCA